CUUUUUUACUGCAGAUUUACUUUAAGGCUCAUAUUCUCCAAGUCUAUUCUGCUUUAAAAAGAAGACAAGAAAAGAAGUGGUUUAUCAAAAUCACGUUAUAAUCAGAUUUUGACCAAGCAUUUUGUAAGUAUACAAAUGUCAGCCAAUGACAUAUAACAACCAUUUCUUAUAAAACCUUGAUGUUCAAAAGCCUGACUAGCAGUGGCAUCCAUGUUGCUUAGGAGUUGGUUUGGAAACAAAGACUUUCAGGCCCUACCUAUACUAGCUAGAUUGCCAAGUAUGCCCACGGACAUGGAACACACAGGACAUUACCUACAUCUUGCCUUUCUGAUGACAACAGUUUUUUCUUUGUCUCCUGGAACAAAAGCAAACUAUACCCGUCUGUGGGCUAACAGUACUUCUUCCUGGGAUUCAGUUAUUCAAAACAAGACAGGCAGAAACCAAAAUGAAAACAUUAACACAAACCCUAUAACUCCUGAAGUAGAUUAUAAAGGUAAUUCUACAAACAUGCCUGAAACAUCUCACAUCGUAGCUUUAACUUCUAAAUCUGAACAGGAGCUUUAUAUACCUUCUGUCGUCAGCAACAGUCCUUCAACAGUACAGAGCAUUGAAAACACAAGCAAAAGUCAUGGUGAAAUUUUCAAAAAGGAUGUCUGUGCGGAAAACAACAACAACAUGGCUAUGCUAAUUUGCUUAAUUAUAAUUGCAGUGCUUUUUCUUAUCUGUACCUUUCUAUUUCUAUCAACUGUGGUUUUGGCAAACAAAGUCUCUUCUCUCAGACGAUCAAAACAAGUAGGCAAGCGUCAGCCUAGAAGCAAUGGCGAUUUUCUGGCAAGCGGUCUAUGGCCCGCUGAAUCAGACACUUGGAAAAGAACAAAACAGCUCACAGGACCCAACCUAGUGAUGCAAUCUACUGGAGUGCUCACAGCUACAAGGGAAAGAAAAGAUGAAGAAGGAACUGAAAAACUUACUAACAAACAGAUAGGUUAGUGAAGAAAAAUGCAAAGUAGCAAUGAGAAGGCUUAUGGAGUAAAAAUGAAGUCAGUUGGUAUUUAAUCCCAAAGUGUUGUUCUGAUUAUCUAAAAUUUGACAUGGUAGACCUUGCAAUUUAGAAUCAAGCAGGUGAGACAGGGAGAAGUAUGCCUGCUUAAUUAUUUAAACUGUGUACUUUUGUUUUGACACUGAAUAUUUUAAAAAGCAAAUAAUAAAAUAACUAAGCAUUUGAGGAAAAUUUUAAGGAUAAAUUGAGGAAACUGAUUAAUAGAGAUAGCAAGGGAUAAUUAAAUAAAUAUUCCCUAUGUAGCAACAGUGGUUAGAUGAUCUUUGUCUGAAUGUAAUUAAACUUUGAAUAGUUUUAGUGUGUCCUUAAAGCCAAGUAUAUGCUUUAACAUCAAAUGGAAGUCAAAUUCCUAAUGCAUAGAUAGAGAGAGCUAAACUGUGUAAUUUAAUGGUAUCUUCUUUGCUGGAUGUGGCAGAAUCCACACCAGCUUAUCAACCAACACAGCUAAUUUUAGAAUAGAUCCUUUAUCUUUCCAUAUGGCACACGUAAGAAAGUGUUUUUCUACUAUUAAUAUUAAAUUAAAACCUUUACUUUUGUAUAAUAAAUUAAAACUCAGAAUAAACCUGUGACCACGUAUAUUUGCAUUCACUUUAUUACUUUAGAGAACACAUUGUAAAGAUCAAUAAGAAAUAGAGCACAACUAAAAUAAAUAAGAUUUAUAGCCACACCAAUAGGCUAAGUGUAAACGCAAAGUAUGUUUCACUGUUUAUGAUUAAUAAUAUUCAUCUUUUCUAUAAAUACUACUUACUGGAACAUUAACAACAAGUACCAAAGGUUGAUUAAUUUUUGGACUUCAAGGAUGCCAAGUAGCCUAAUGAUUUAUUAGGGGUGUGUGUGUGUGUGUGUGUGUGUGUGUGUGUGUGUGUGUGUGUUCAAAUCUGGAAAACUGCAUACUUCAGGUUAUAAUUUAACCUUUAAAGAAACUGGCUUCAAGUAAAAUAAUGACUUACAUUUAAGUUGAGAACCCCCCAUCUUCAAUUAAAUAUAUUACAAAAAUUGGUUUGAGAGACUUUCCAAAUAUCUACUGAAAUUAACACAGGGCUAAGAUCAGGCCACAUUUCAAAAAUCUCAUCCCUUACUGGGCAUUUAUUUCGGGCAAUAUAGUAACCAUUUUAAAAAUAUUUUUUAUAUGUUUUUUCCCAAGUAUGACUACAAUCUUACUCUCCCUUCUAAGCUAGUGAUUCUUACCCUGGCUGCAUGUCAGAAUCACCUGAAGAGUUUUUAAAAAACACCAAUGCCUAAUUCCCAUGUCUUCCUUCUGAUGCAACUGGAAUGGGGUGAACUCUAAGCAUUGGUAAUUUUUACGUAACUCUCAAGGUGAUAACUGCUCUUGGUCAUCAAAUUCAAACGUCUAGCUAUUAUUAAAAUGAGAGGAAAAAAAUAAAGCAUCAUUUUUAUUAUCAAUUUAUUAGCAAUUUGUAAAAAACAAAUCUAUUCUCUAAACGAGAAAUCAUAACAAUAUUAUUCCAGAUAAAGUUAAGUGUUAACAAAGUAAAAAGGAAAGCAUGAGAAUAUUCAUGCCAGUCAUGGUGACUGAAAUCAGGUUAUCUUUUGAGGGGAAAAAUAACCCAGAUUAGAAAUGAAACUGGGCAGACUUCCCAUUCUGUGCAAAAAUUGAAAAUUUGAGAUUGUGCACCAGUACAUCCAGGAGUAACACAAAGCACUCCUUGAAUCAAGGGUCAUAAAUAAACACUUGUCAGAGAAAAUUAAAAGAAAUUAAUAUCAUCAUAAAAAUAGGAAAUUACUUUCAUAUUCAACAUACUGGUCAAACAUUUUCUCACCAGAGAGCUUCUACCACAAGGAUAUUUAAAAGAAUAUUUAAAAUUCACC